AGGCAACGGGGCGGCGCAGGCAGGAGGGAACGGCUGGUUGCAGGUUUCUCUCGCCCUGGUCCCGCGCGGCCCCGCCGAGGCGGCGACCAAGGUGGGUGCGGGGACUCUCGGGAGCCGUGGGCCAGGCGCUUAGCCGGCCACCUCGGGCCCUGUCCAGGCCCAGGCGUUCCAGGGCUGCUCUGCGGGCCGCGUGCGAGAGGGACUCUCGGGAGGCCCCGGGGCGCCGCACCCACUCCUUCCCACUUGGGACUCCCGCGGGCGCCCGGCUCUCGCUCCUCUGGCCAGCGUGGGCCUCCCAGGCCCCCUCGCGGCUCUCUCCAGAGCAGGAGCCCCACCUUGGGCCGCCCCUCUCACACCUGCCGUGGGUCUGGUACGCGCCUCUGUGUCGGACUCCGCGCCCGCCUGCGUGGGAGGAAGCCAGGACUCCCGGGCGACCGGGCCAUUCCUGUGGUUUGUGUCAGUUCCACAGCAGCACGUGGGCACUUUCCACCGUCAGCCACUGGGCAGCCCGGGGCACUCCUGCAGCGUCCCCUGGCCCUCUCCAGGGCAGGGGAAGGUUGGGCAGUCCUGGGCGGCCAGCACCCCGGCGUGCAUGUCUCCUGAGCAGCUGCCCAUCGGGCCUCUGCUGGCCUGGGGGCUCCAAGAUGCAAGGCCGGCGGGAGCUGGGGGGAGAGCCUUUGAGUGACCUCCAGGAGGAAGCAGCCAGCGCUUCCCUCCGAGUGGCACCUGAGAGGCUGAGUGAUGACAGUUUGGAAUGGAGACGGACCUGCCCCGACCUUCUCCUGUCCGAUGGGAAAGCCAGCAUCUCCAUGCCCCGUGAGGGCGGUUCCACCUGCACUGCCCGAUGUCCUGACCCUGGGGAACACAGCAGCACUUGGGGGGAGUUUGAAGGCUUUCGGGAAUCUUCAGCCAAGUCUGGACAAUUCUCACAGUCCCUUGAACUCCUCGAGGGACCCACAGAACCCCAGCCACCGAGAACCACUUCUGCCCCAAAAGAGUGCAGUUCUCACCAACCAUGCCAGGGUGGACCUUGGGUGACAGGAACUUCUGCCGUCCCACCUUCUGAGCCCAUUCUCAGCUAUGAGAACAUUUUAAAGUGUGCUUUUCAAGAAAUAACAGUCCAGCAGGCAGCUGAAGACGUUUCCACCAUAGACCAUUUCCUAGAAAUAAGCAGUGAAGAAAAACCUGGCGUUGAACGUGUACAUAAAUUGUGUAACGAAUCCAGAAAACUCUGGAGAGCCCUUCAGAGCAUACACACCACGUCUACUUCUCAGCGCCUCUGGAGCGAGUCCCGUUGCCAGGAGAACUUCUUUCUUGUUCUCGGAAUAGAUGCUGCGCAGAAGAACCUUUCUGGAGGCCAGGGCCACAUCAUGGAAGAUUGUGACCUCAAAGAGCCUGAAGGACUCCUCACUGUCAGCAGCUUCUGUCUCCAGCAUUGCAAAGCCCUGAUCCAGACCAAGAGGCCCUGAAGGAACGUGACCAUCACCUGACCUGAGUGACACUGCAAAGCCCUCAUUCUUUCUAGUGGACGUGGAGCUCUCUCCAAGCAGAUAACUGAGCCGUCAGCCACAUCAGAGGCCAGGGACAUGGCCUUCAGAGGCUUUGGCCAUCAUGCAAAAAACCUGGCCACCCUGAAGCCUCUAUGCUGGAGAAAUGUCUGCAGUGAUCCCACAGAGAUGCUGACAAGAUGCCCAAGGACCCAGCUGCUGGAGCUUUCCGGCCAGCAUGCCAGCCCUGGGAGGAGGGAAGCCUUCAGGGUGGGGUGCAUCCAGCUGCAGCUGCUGCCUGACAGCAGUGGCCUGACAGAUCCCAGCAAGAACCACCCGGCUGAGCCCAGCCAAGCCGUGGCAUGAGAUCAUGGCAGUAACAGAUGGUAGGUGCUGCAUGCUGUGAAGCUAGUGAUGGCAGCUACACAGCAGGAGGUCAUGAAAACAACACAUGUCCAGAUAACCAGUGGGUCCAUAGAGGUCACUGGAAACUUAGUAAUUGAAACUGAAUAAUGAAAAUGGCACUGAUCAAAAUCUGAGUGAAUGCAGUGCAUAGAAGGAAAUUUAUAGCUUUAAAUGUUUAUAUUAGAAAGUAAGAAAAGUACAAAACCACCUAAGAUUUCAUGUUAAUGUGCAAGAAAAAGAGCAAAUUAAACCAAAAGUAAGCAGAAAGAAGGAAAUAAAACUGAGUGCCAAAAUCAACAAAAUGGAAAAUGGCAGAACACUAGGAAAAAGGGAUGGUCCUAAGUGAAGACGUAAGAGCAUGUGAUGUGCAGCUCUCGCAUGACUCCUGAUUCAAACAAACCAAAUGUAGAGACAACUUCGAAUAACACACAGCGAGGAAAAGCAGGCAGCCUCUGCCCAACACAGCCAGGAGACAGCCUCGGAAAUCGGAGAAAAUAUUUGGAAACCAUAUGUCUGAUAAGGGGUUAAUAUCCAAAAUACAUAAGGAACUCAAACAACGUAACAGGAAGAAAACCCAGAUAACCUGAUUGAAAAAAUAGGAAAAGGACCUGAACAGACAUUUUUUCUUUCUUUCUUUCUUUUUUUUUUUUGCUGUGUCGCCCAGGCUGGGGUGCAAUGGUGCAAUGUUAGCUCACUGCAAACUCUGCCUCCUGAGUACAAGUGAUUGUCCUGCCUCAGCCUCCCGAGUAGCUGGGACUACAGGCGCCCGCCACCAUGCCCGGCUAAUUUUUGUAUUUUUAGUAGAGACAGGGUUUCACCAUGUUGGCCAGGCUGGUCUCGAACUCCUGACCUCAGGUGAUCCACCUGCCUCGGCCUCCCAAAGUGCUGGGAUUACAGGCGUGAGCCACCGCGUCCAGCCAAGCAGACAUUUUCCAAAAAUAUAUAUAUAUCUAUUUUUAUAUAUAUACACACACACAAAUGACCAACAGCUAUACAAAACCAAUGCUCCAUAUCAGUAAUCAUCAGGGAAAUGCAAAUCAAGACUGCAAUAAGAUACCCCCUCACACCUGUUAGGAUGGCUAUUCUAAACAGAUGAAAUGUCGGUGAUGGUGUAGAGAAAUGGGAAUGCUUGUGCACUGUUGGUGGGAGUGUAAAGUAGUACCGCCGCUAUGGAAAACAGUAUGGAGGUGUCUGAAAAAGUUAAAAAUAGAACUACCAUAUCAUCUAGCAAUCCCACUACUGGGUAUUUAUCCAAUGGAAAGGAAAUCAGUAUGUUGAAGAGAUACCCGCACCCCCAUGUUUAUUGCAGCACUAGUCACCAUAGCCAAGCUAUGGAACCAACCUAGGUGUCCAACAACAGAUGAAUGGAUAAAGAAAAUGUGGUACAUACGCACAAUGGGAUACUAUUCAGCUGUAAAAAAAAAAAAAAAAAAAAAAUGAAAUCCUCUCAUUUGCAACUGUCUAGAUGAACCUGAAGCAUUUAUGCUAAGCGAAAUAAGCUGGUACAGAAAGACAAACCCCACGUGAUCUCACUCAUACGUGGAACCCAAAAAGUCAAACUCGCCAGGUGUGGUGGCUCAUGCCUGUAAUCCCAGCACUUUGGGAGGCCAAGGCAAGAGGAU